ACUGAGGUCACCCUCCAGGCUGUGGAACCUUUGUUCUUUCACUCUUUGCAAUAAAUCUUGCUGCUGCUCACUCUUUGGGUCCACACUGCCUUUAUGAGCUGUAACACUCACUGGGAAUGUCUGCAGCUUCACUCCUGAAGCCAGCGAGACCACGAACCCACCAGGAGGAACAAACAACUCCAGACGCGCAGCCUUAAGAGCUGUAACACUCACCGCGAAGGUCUGCAGCUUCACUCCUGAGCCAGCCAGACCACGAACCCACCAGAAGGAAGAAACUCCAAACACAUCCGAACAUCAGAAGGAGCAAACUCCUGACACGCCACCUUUAAGAACCGUGACACUCAACGCUAGGGUCCGCGGCUUCAUUCUUGAAGUCAGUGAGACCAAGAACCCACCAAUUCCGGACACGCUAAUUGUUGUAGAUCAUCACUUCAAGGUGCCCAUAUCUUUCUAGUGGAAAAAUUAUUCUGGCCUCCGCUGCAUACAAAUCAGGCAACCAGAAUUCUACAUAUAUAAGGCAAAGUAACAUCCUAGACAUGGCUUUAGAGAUCCACAUGUCAGACCCCAUGUGCCUCAUCGAGAACUUUAAUGAGCAGCUGAAGGUUAAUCAGGAAGCUUUGGAGAUCCUGUCUGCCAUUACGCAACCUGUAGUUGUGGUAGCGAUUGUGGGCCUCUAUCGCACUGGCAAAUCCUACCUGAUGAACAAGCUGGCUGGGAAGAACAAGGGCUUCUCUGUUGCAUCUACGGUGCAGUCUCACACCAAGGGAAUUUGGAUAUGGUGUGUGCCUCAUCCCAACUGGCCAAAUCACACAUUAGUUCUGCUUGACACCGAGGGCCUGGGAGAUGUAGAGAAGGCUGACAACAAGAAUGAUAUCCAGAUCUUUGCACUGGCACUCUUACUGAGCAGCACCUUUGUGUACAAUACUGUGAACAAAAUUGAUCAGGGUGCUAUCGACCUACUGCACAAUGUGACAGAACUGACAGAUCUGCUCAAGGCAAGAAACUCACCCGACCUUGACAGGGUUGAAGAUCCUGCUGACUCUGCGAGCUUCUUCCCAGACUUAGUGUGGACUCUGAGAGAUUUCUGCUUAGGCCUGGAAAUAGAUGGGCAACUUGUCACACCAGAUGAAUACCUGGAGAAUUCCCUAAGGCCAAAGCAAGGUAGUGAUCAAAGAGUUCAAAAUUUCAAUUUGCCCCGUCUGUGUAUACAGAAGUUCUUUCCAAAAAAGAAAUGCUUUAUCUUUGACUUACCUGCUCACCAAAAAAAGCUUGCCCAACUUGAAACACUGCCUGAUGAUGAGCUAGAGCCUGAAUUUGUGCAACAAGUGACAGAAUUCUGUUCCUACAUCUUUAGCCAUUCUAUGACCAAGACUCUUCCAGGUGGCAUCAUGGUCAAUGGAUCUCGUCUAAAGAACCUGGUGCUGACCUAUGUCAAUGCCAUCAGCAGUGGGGAUCUGCCUUGCAUAGAGAAUGCAGUCCUGGCCUUGGCUCAGAGAGAGAACUCAGCUGCAGUGCAAAAGGCCAUUGCCCACUAUGACCAGCAAAUGGGCCAGAAAGUGCAGCUGCCCAUGGAAACCCUCCAGGAGCUGCUGGACCUGCACAGGACCAGUGAGAGGGAGGCCAUUGAAGUCUUCAUGAAAAACUCUUUCAAGGAUGUAGACCAAAGUUUCCAGAAAGAAUUGGAGACUCUACUAGAUGCAAAACAGAAUGACAUUUGUAAACGGAACCUGGAAGCAUCCUCGGAUUAUUGCUCGGCUUUACUUAAGGAUAUUUUUGGUCCUCUAGAAGAAGCAGUGAAGCAGGGAAUUUAUUCUAAGCCAGGAGGCCAUAAUCUCUUCAUUCAGAAAACAGAAGAACUGAAGGCAAAGUACUAUCGGGAGCCUCGGAAAGGAAUACAGGCUGAAGAAGUUCUGCAGAAAUAUUUAAAGUCCAAGGAGUCUGUGAGUCAUGCAAUAUUACAGACUGACCAGGCUCUCACAGAGACGGAAAAAAAGAAGAAAGAGGCACAAGUGAAAGCAGAAGCUGAAAAGGCUGAAGCGCAAAGGUUGGCGGCGAUUCAAAGGCAGAACGAGCAAAUGAUGCAGGAGAGGGAGAGACUCCAUCAGGAACAAGUGAGACAAAUGGAGAUAGCCAAACAAAAUUGGCUGGCAGAGCAACAGAAAAUGCAGGAACAACAGAUGCAGGAACAGGCUGCACAGCUCAGCACAACAUUCCAAGCUCAAAAUAGAAGCCUUCUCAGUGAGCUCCAGCACGCCCAGAGGACUGUUAAUAACGAUGAUCCAUGUGUUUUACUCUAAAGUGCUAAAUAUGGGAGUUUCCUUUUUUUACUCUUUGUCACUGAUGACACAACAGAAAAGAAACUGUAGACCUUGGGACAAUCAACAUUUAAAUAAACUUUAUAAUUAUUUUUUCAAACUUUCAUAUAGAGUUAUAAGAUUAUGAUGCUGGUAUCUGGUAAAAUGUACAUCCCAGUAGUCCAAUAGUUUAAAUGUUUAUUGCUUCCUUUAAGAGAUUAUAAAUUGUAUAAGGGACAUUGUAUCACUGCCUUCAUUUAUGCGUGAUAUUGGGAUGGUUUCAUCAGGAGAUGCUUUCCUUGCAUCUCAAUGUCAUCUGUCUAAUUUCUCAUAAGGGGAUUAUGUUACCUAGAGCAGGGCUUCCCAACCCUCAGGCCAUAGACUAGCUCUGAUCUGUGGCCUCUUAGGAACCCGGCCACACAGCAGGAGGUGAGCAGCAGGUAAGUGAGCAUUACAGCCUGAGCUCCACCUCCUGUCAGAUCAGCAGUGACAUUAGAUUCUCACAGGAGUGGGAACCCUAUUGUGAACUGUGCAUGCAAAAGAUCUAGGUUGUGUGAUCCUUGUGGAACAAUAUAAACCAGAAACCAAUAACGCCACCCCACCUCCAACCCCCGCCAACCCUCUGUGGAAAAAUUACCUUCCACGAAACUGGUCCCUGAUGCCAAAUAGGUUGGGGGACCGCUGACCUAGAGGGAGUUAUGCACAUGGGCUUAUAAGGUUAGCCAAGAGAAAGGACAAGAAGACCCAAAGUCGGCAAGCAAAUUUAUUAACCUGCUGGGCUGCUCUACAGAAAUCUGAGGAGGCAGACACCGGGCUUACAGGCUAAGGGGUAUAAGUAGGUCUGCAGGGGUUUUGUGUGUGUGUGCGGGGGUGUCGGGGGGGCAAGGCCAUUUGUGGAGACUUUUCCUCCCAGUAUGGCCACAUCCUGCAGUUUGUCAGUUUUUGCCCCCGCCUGGCUCAGGGUACCAGGAUGUGGUUUAGCUUAGGGGUGGUUAUAGUGGCACCUAAGUUCUGGGAACUUGCGGUGGGGGCGACCUUUUGGACGAAAAAUAAGCUGCAGGGCAGCUAGGGGAGGGGGCUUGUUAUAUUCCUCUGGGGGCAGGGUGUCCCUAACUGGGCUCAGUCGGAAGGAACUUGACCAAAGUCUGGGCUCAGUUGGGCAUCACUCAGGCUAAUGGUCGUGUGCUGGAUGCCAUCAGAGGGAAGUACCAAUGGUAAAGUGGAAACAAUGUGCAGCUUUCAACUGGGUGGAGGCUGCUAUUCUGUGGACAGUGAGAUGUUUCCUUGGCACUGUCAAUAGACAAUCUGCGUAGAGAAAUUCCAAGCUGAAAGCCAAUAAUGUUAUAAUAAAAUAGAGAUUCUUCAGAAGAUGAAAGGAAUUACCAGCAUGGAAAUUGUGUCAUAGGCUUAAGGGCUAAAGAAGAAGCCUUUUCUUUUCUGUUCACCCUCACCAAGAGCACAACUUAAAUAGGGCAUUUUAUAACCUGAACACAAUUUAUAUUGGACUUAAUUAUUAUGUGUAAUAUGUUUAUAAUCCUUUAGAUCUUAUAAAUAUGUGGUAUAAGGAAUGCCAUAUAAUGUGCCAAAAAUCUGAGUGCAUUUAAUUUAAUGCUUGCUUAUAGUGCUAAAGUUAAAUGAUCUUAAUUCUUUGCAAUUAUAUAUGAAAAAUGACUGAUUUUUCUUAAAAUAUGUAACUUAUAUAAAUAUAUCUGUUUGUACAGAUUUUAACCAUAAAAACAUUUUUGGAAAACCAUAAAUCAGUUCCUUUGUUUGUAUUUUUCUCAAAGUUAAAAGUCUAUAGAGAAAGACUGAAUUUCCCUAAGGAGAUUAAGAAUUGCUUUAAGACUAGAAUUAAAACACACUUUAUUACAUCUUUUUAUGUACUUUUUGUUACUUUGUUUUGUAUAUCUCCAGUAAAAUUUUUUUUGUUUAAAUUAUAGAAACAUUACACAAAGCUCUGUUUUUCUCCCUUAUAAGUACUUACUCAUAUAAGGAAUUUUCCACUUAGGUAAUAUGAUAGGAGCUUGAAUUUUUUUAGUCACCCAAAAUAUGAUUUACUUAUAUACAGAAAAAAGCCGAAAAAUUUUAGUGUCUGCUCUUUUUACUGUUCUUUGAAGAGCUUUAAUAUGAGGAAUUUUUCAUAUCAGAUAGGAUGUGGUGCUACUCAGCAGUAUUUCUAGAUUUGAACUGAAGUUCAGAAGGUACCAGCAUAUUCAACUGAGCAUUUGUCUAGCAAUACCCUACAAUUACCUUUUCAAGCUGUGCAAUUUAUAAAGAAAAAAAUACAUUUUAUCAUCCAAGGAAAUGUUAUCAGUAAAAAGAAUAGCUCUAUCUCCAAAUUAAAUAUUGAUAUCUUUAUUACCCAUCUUAAAGAAAUUUUUUAAAAUCCUGAGACUCAGAAAAUUAAGUCAUUUAAGGUUUCACACCUUGUUACUGUUAACCUAGACCAUGUUACAAAGUAGUUGAUUUCUAGUCUAAUUUAACUUUUGCUAUUAUAUCUCCCCCACCAAAAACCAGAGAGGCAUGCUGCUUUCAUUAGUGAUCCACAGAUAUUCUUCCCCACCAGCUUCCCUGGAUCCCACUCAUCCCCAAAUACUCUGAUCUCACAGGUUAGAGAUCUGUCACUGGGUGCAAAAGAACAAGAAAAGGCACUGUAAGGUAAACAUUGAUGAUUUCUUGAAACUACCAGUAAGUAGCUUAUAUUUUCUGACUUUCUUUGUCUUACUGUUGUGAAAUCAACUGAUCUAGUUUUAAAUGUAAUGAAAAGCAAAGCAAUAGAUUCUCCCCUAGAGCCUGCAGAUGGAAUGCAGCCUUGUUAACAUCUUGAUUUAAGCUUCACAGACUUCUGAUUUCCAAAACUGUAAGAUAAUAAGCUUCUGUUGUUUUAAGCCACAAAAUUAGUAAUAAUUUGUUAUAGCAGCAAUAGGAAACAAGUACAAAAUCUUUAUUAGUUAAUACUAUGAAUAGUUAUUCAUACCAGCUAAGAGAUAUUUGGAAUUUAUUAUGGAUCACUUUAUUAUGGUCACUGUAGUAAUUCACCUGUUGCUCAUAAAAACCUUAUAAACAUUUAGUAUUGUUUUAUGGCAAUUGUUAUUUUAAACAAUAUUAUCAAUGUAUGUUAGUGUUAUCAUUAUUAAAGUUAUUAUUGUUAAAGCAUUGAAAUUAAAUAAAUUAAGGUCAGUACCACAGAAGGCCUUUUGAAUUUAGAACCCACAUUAAUAACCAUCUUGUGGUACUUUCUUAUCUUGCUUAGUGAUACGGUUUGGCUGUGUCCACUCAAAUCUCAUCUUGAAUUAUGGCUCCCAUAAUGCCCACGUGUUGUGGGAGGGACCAGGUGGGAGGUAAUCAAAUCAUGGGGGUGGGUUUUCAUGUGCUUUUUUCAUGAUAGUGAAUAAGUCGCCUGAGAUCUGAUGGCUUCAUAAAGGGCAAUUCCCCUGCACAUGCUCUCUUGCCUGACACCAUGUAAGAUGUGCCUUUGUUCCUCUUUCAUCUUCUGCUGUGGUUGUGAGGCCUCCCCACCCAUGUGAAACUACAAGUCCAUUACAUCUCUUUUCCUUUAUAAAUUACCCAGUCUUGAGUAUUUCUUCAUAGCAGUAUGAAAAUGGACUAAUAUACUUAGGAAAACAUAGAAAUACUGAAUAAUGUGUUAAAAUUUAGAAGGAAUUACUAAAAUAAUUGAAAUCAAAAGCAUAGAUUCAAAACAAUGUAUAAGAAUUCAGCACAAAAUAAGCAGGUAAAGAAAUUUCUAAAAUGAAGUAGAGAAAAUGUGGUAAUGACUCUAGUGUAUAACGAUCACCAACAGAAUAGAAAGUCCAAAAAAUAGACUUUAUAGGAAUAAUACAGGGUAAAGAUAGACUUCUUAGUAGGUUGGGACUACUGGAUGGCCAUAUAGGAAAAGAUCAAGUUGUAACCAGACCUCACACACAAUACACUAAAAUAAGAAAAAGGAACCACACCCAAAUUGAUAAAAUAUAAAAUGUAAAACUAUGAAAAUGCAUUUGAAGAAAUCAAGGUUAUGUUCUUCAUAAACCUGUAGAGGAGAGGGCCUUUCUAAAUGUGACUCAAAACUCUUGAAAUCUCUCUUGACCCCAUGUCUCAGUCAGUUUCAACACAAUCUUUGUUCCCUUUCAAAGCAAUAUUUUAGUUAGUUACAUCCCAUUCUCUGUUUUUCAAAAUUAUUAAAUGUGACACAUACUGAAGAGUACAAAAAACAUAAAAUGUACAAUAUUCAAUAUAAAUAAAUUACAAGAUGAACGCACAAGUAACAACCCAGGUACAUACAUUCAGCAUUACUAAAAUUCUAUAGGUGUAUAUGACAACUUCUGACAACCCUGCUAGAGCCAACUAAUAUCACAACUUUCACAACUAUUUUCUAGGAUUUUAUUAUAAACAUGUGAGCUCCUAAGUAAUGUAAUUUUGUUUGGCCUGUUUUCAAACUUUAUUUAAAUGGAAUUACAUUGUUUGUAUUCUUUUAUGCCUUGCUUCAUUUGUUAAUAAAAUCUUUAUAAGAUUCAUCUA